GGGAACCCUCCAUGGGCUUCCUGUGUUCCCCAGGACAAAAGCCCAACUCCUCACUGUCACUCCACAGCCCUGUGUCCAGGGCCCCUGCCACUGUCCAGGCUCCUCCUGGGAACUUGCCCUCAUCUCAUGACUCCCUCUGCCCCAGUCACAUUUGCUUUUCUCUUUUCCCAAACAUCAAAACCCUUCCCGUCUCAGGUCAUUUUCACUGCUCUUACCCUAUUUCUCUAAAUGCUCACAGCACUGUCCCUUUCUCCUUCAGGUCCUGGCUCAGAAAUGUCUCCCAUGCCCUCCCACCCCCAACUGAAUUUCCCUCUGCCCAUCAGUCUCUAUCACAUUACUCAGGUUUUAUUAUCUCUGUGUCAGUCACAUCAGAAACACACUUUUUUUCUUUUUCCAAAGAGUCUCGCUCUGUCCUCCAGGCUGUGAGUGCAGUCUUGUGAUCUUGGCUCACUGCAACCUUUGUCUCCUGAGUUCAAGCAAUUCUUGUGCCUUAGUCUCCCAAGUAGCUGAGAUUACAGGAUUGACUUCUAAAGACUUGGUACGUGAGGAAAAAACACGGAAGAGGAAGAGGAAAGCAAAGGAGUCAGGGAUGGCUCUUCUUCAGGGUCUACUGACAUUCAGGGAUGUGGCCAUAGAAUUCUCUCAGGAGGAGUGGAAAUGCCUGGACCCUGCUCAGAGGACUCUAUACAGAGACGUGAUGCUGGAGAAUUAUAGGAACCUGGUCUCCCUGGAUACCUCUUCCAAAUGCAUGAUGAAGAUGUUCUCAUCAACAGGACAAGGCAAUACAGAAGUGGUCCACACAGGGACAUUGCAAAUACAUGCAAGUCAUCACAUUGGAGAUACUUGCUUCCAGGAAAUUGAGAAAGAUAUUCAUGACUUUGUGUUUCAGUGGCAAGAAAAUGAAACAAAUGGCCAUGAAGCACUCAUGACAAAAACCAAAAAGUUGAUGAGUAGUACAGAGCGACAUGAUCAAAGGCAUGCUGGAAACAAACCUAUUAAAAAUGAGCUUGGAUCAAGCUUUCAUUCGCAUCUGCCUGAAGUGCACAUAUUUCACCCCGAAGGGAAAAUUGGUAAUCAAGUUGAGAAGGCUAUCAACGAUGCUUUCUCAGUUUCAGCAUCCCAACGAAUUUCCUGUAGGCCAAAAACUCGUAUUUCUAAUAAGUAUAGGAAUAAUUUCCUCCAGUCUUCAUUACUCACACAAAAACGGGAAGUACACACAAGAGAAAAAUCUUUCCAACGUAAUGAGAGUGGCAAAGCCUUUAAUGGUAGCUCACUCUUAAAAAAACAUCAGAUAAUCCAUUUAGGAGACAAACAGUAUAAAUGUGAUGUAUGCGGCAAGGACUUUCAUCAGAAGCGAUACCUUGCAUGCCAUAGAUGUCACACUGGUGAGAAUCCUUACACGUGUAAUGAGUGUGGCAAGACAUUCAGUCACAAUUCAGCCCUGUUAGUUCACAAGGCAAUUCAUACUGGAGAGAAACCUUACAAGUGUAAUGAAUGUGGCAAGGUUUUUAAUCAACAAUCAAACCUUGCACGUCAUCAUAGAGUUCAUACUGGAGAGAAACCUUACAAAUGUGAAGAAUGUGACAAAGUUUUCAGUCGCAAAUCACACCUUGAAAGACAUAGGAGAAUUCACACUGGAGAGAAACCAUACAAAUGUAAGGUUUGUGACAAGGCUUUCAGACGUGAUUCACACCUGGCACAACAUACUGUAAUUCACACUGGAGAGAAACCUUACAAGUGUAAUGAGUGUGGCAAGACCUUUGUUCAAAAUUCAUCUCUUGUAAUGCAUAAGGUCAUUCAUACUGGAGAGAAACGUUACAAGUGUAAUGAAUGUGGCAAGGUUUUUAAUCACAAAUCAAACCUUGCAUGUCAUCGUAGACUUCAUACUGGAGAGAAACCUUACAAGUGUAAUGAAUGUGGCAAGGUUUUUAAUCGAAAAUCAAACCUUGAACGUCAUCAUAGACUUCAUACUGGAAAGAAAUCUUAGAAGUGUAAAUUUGCAAGGUUUUUAGGCAACAGUCAAACCUUGCAUGUCAUCAUAGACUUUAUACUGGAGAGAAACCUUACAAAUGUGAAGAAUGUGACAAAAGUUUUCAAUUUCAAAUCACUCCUUGAAAUACAUAGGAGAGUUCAUACUGGAGAGAAACCAUACAAAUGUAAGGUUUGUGACAAGGAUUUCGGGUGUGAUUCACACCUGGCCCAACAUACUGGAAUUCACACUGGAAAGGAACUGUACAAGUGUAAUGAGUGUGGCAGAGCCUUUGGUGGUCAGUCAACACUUACUCACCAUCAAGCAAUCCAUGGUAUAGGGAAACUUGACUAAUGUAAUGAUUGUCACAAAGUCUUCAGUAAUAUUACAGCCAUUGCAAAACAUUGGAGAAUCCAUAAUGAAGGAGGUCUUACAAGUGUAAUAAAUGUGGCAAGUUUUUCAGACAUCAUUCAUAACUUGCAGUUCAUUGGCGAUCUUAUACAGGAGAGAAAUCUUACAAAUGUGAUGAUUGUGGCAAGGUCUUCAGUCAAGCUUCAUCUUUUGCAAAACGGGAGAAUUCAUACAGGAGAGAAACCUCACAAGUGUGAUGAUUGUGAGCAAAGCCUUUACUUCACGUUCACACCACAUUAGAUAUCAGAGGAUCCAUACUGGACAGAAAUCUUACAAACGUCCUAUGUGUGGCAAGGUCUUCAGUCCGAGGUUACUCCUUGCAGAAUAUCAUAACGUUCAUUUUUGAGGUAAUAGUUACAAAUGCGGUGAGCACAGCAAACCAUCAAGGAUUGACAGUAGAGUCAAUUCAGAAUUGACUUGAGUUUGAGUUGACUUAAAACAUUCAGUUGAAGCAUUAAUUGACAUUAAAGUGUUUAUGUUAAGAGGAUUGGGCCAGGCGUGUGGCUCACGCCUGUAAAUCCAGCACUUUAGGAGCCCAAGGUGGAUAGAUCACUUGAGGUCAUGAGUUUGAGAUCAGCCUGGCCAACAGACGUGAGUCACUUUUCCCAGCCUGCUUUUUGUUUCUUUAACAAAAACCAAUAGGGGUUUUUAUAGGUAUUGUGUUGAAUCUGAAUCACAUUGGCUUAUAUAAUAACAAUAUUGAUUUUUCCAAACCAUCAAUGUGGGUUGUAUAUAUAUGUUUUUAAUCAUUUUGGUUAAUGUUUGUAGAUUUCAAGGUGUGAAAUUCUCAGUUUUUUUAUGUUUAUUCCUAAGUAUUUCUUACUUUAAGAUCUCUAGCAAAUGGAAGUGUUUUUUAAUUUUCGUUUAAAUUUUUUAUUGUUUAUGGAAAUUCAAUUAAUUUUUGGUGCUGCUAUUGCAUUGUGCAAAUCCACUGAAUGUGUUGAUUAGUUCCAGUAGUAUUUUGGUUGACUCAGGCCCCGCCCACCUCUUCGCCUCCCGUCUGGCCUGACCCAGGCCCCGCCCACCUCCUCGGGGGUCUCCCCGCGGGUCUGGCUUCUGUACUGUGCUGAUUGGCACAGACCCGGAAGCUGAUGGCAUGGACUGAAGGUUGCCCCGUUGAGUUUGCGCUUCCCAGUUCUCUGGUACUGCUAUACCGGGGACGUGGGUGUCUCCACAGACCUGGAAAUUCCGGCCCCUCUUUCUCAACUCAGAGCAAAUUGAGACGUCCGGGUGGGAGUCCGUGAGUCUUUUCCUUUUGAGUUUAAAGUCGCCCUGAGGCUGGUCCCGUCCCGGUCUUUUCUGCAGUAGGGCCGUGCAGACACCUCCUGUAGCGAAACUUUCCUUCUCAAAACCCUUCCCGACCCGUCCUCCCGCCUCGCGCUGUUUCAGGUCCUCACCAGCGAGUUGGACUCUCGCCCUGGGCUCCUCAUCGGCGCCUGGAGGGCAGCGCUGCAGCCCCACUCCCGGGAAGGCCGCGUCCUCUGCCUGGUCCUGGGAUCCUGCAGACCCCACCCCUGUCCGAAGGCGCCAUCGCCCACCACCUCCCUCCUCGUGCCGGCCCUGCUUCUCCCCAGUUCCAACCCCAGGAAAACGUGCUUCUCCUGGAGGCAACCCUCUUUUUCCACCCUCGCCCUGUUGUUCCCGGAAGGCAGGCCUGGAAUGUGAAGUUUCCAGGUAGAUGGAUAUUAAACAUAGAAUUGAAGAAAAAAAAAAAAACCCCACAAAGUAACAAAAGAAUGAAGCGGCGAAAGCAGAAAUUUACUCAACCAAGAAAGCACCCCACAGGGUGGGGGUGGGCCCAAGCGAGCGUCUCCAGGGCCCCAUUUACAAAGUUUUUGGAGGUUAUUUUUUUUUGAGGUCCCUAUGGGCUACCCCUUAUCUGGAUGAAGAAUUUGGCCCUUGGCCAAGGAAAUAACUGAGGUAAAUUGGCCUGAGGCCAGAGCAGAUGGGUGCCCUAUGCAGAUGAAGGGGUGGCCGGUGCUUGGCCUUGGCCACUCCUGGGCUCUUUCUCUUUCCACCUGCGACCUGGUGGAAGGGGGAGGGUGUUAGGGAGAGUAGCCUUUGAUCCUUUGUUACUUUGGGUGGGAAGAUGGGGUUUUUCCUUUUAGUCUAGUUUUGGAAAGUUCGCGUUAAUUGGUUUUAGAUUCCCUGCCUCCCUAGACCCAGGACCCAUGUGGUUUUUUUUGUUUUUGUUUUUGUUUUUUUGAUGGAGAUGGGGUCUUACUCUGCUGCGCAGGCCGAAGAGCGGUGACCGGAUCACAGCUCACUGCAGCUUCAACCUCCUGGGCUCAAGGGAUCCUCCCACCUCAGCCUGCAGAGUAGCUGGGACCACAGCCGCGCGCCACCACACCGCGCCAAUUUUUGUGUUCUUGGUAGAGACCGGGUUUUGCCUUGUUGUCUAGGUUGGGCUCCAACUGCAGGGCUAAAGCGAUCCAAGAGCAUCAGCCUCCCAAAGUGCUGGGAUUACAGGCUUGAGCCACCAUGCCCGCCUUAUUUCUUAAUUUAAAAAAAAAAAUGUAUAUGUAGACUGAACGCGGUGGCUCAUGCCUGUCAUCCCAGCACUUUGUGAGGCCGAUUCUCCUCUAUCCAGGAGACGGGUUUCACCAUUUUGCCAGGUUUGUCUCAAACUCCUCGGCUUAACUGAUCCGCUUGCUUUGGCCUUCCAAAGUGCUAGGAUUACAGGAGUGAGCCACCACACGUAGCCAGUCCUGGCAUUUUGUAGAAGGAUGGCCAACGCAGCCUGUUGACCCUUCCUGGCCAUCACAUGAAAAUCAGCGACUCUUCCUUCUUACAAAACUCGGAGCUUCUCAGGAUAACUUGGUGAAACGUCCCCCGCUGUGAACCUCAGUGAGCCCACCUGUAAUAUACAGGUGAGGGAGAAGACCAGAAAAGCUCAGUCAGAGUGACACUGACCCCUGAAAUGAUGGGCACAAUGGAGUGUGUGGCUUUUCCUGUAGGACAGGGAGGUAUUUAGUUGUAGUUUGAACUUUAAAGGAUUCCAGUCCUCCGAAAAACAGGAUUAGACUCAAAUCACCUUGAACCUUAUCAUCUCAUGGCUUUGACCCACCUACAUGGCUCCGUGUCCCCUGCAGGCCUCGCCCCGGAGCUCUACAAUCCUGUGUGCAGUUGUCUCCGCAGCUCUCUGCUGGGACAUCAAACAGGCAUCUCCACCUUCAUGUGUCUAUAAGUGACUUCCUAAACCCCCAAACACAUUCCCUUACAGUCCUACACAUCUCAGAUGAGGGUGACAGUGUACUUCUGGGUGCUUAGCUGAGGUUGACACCAUGUAUUUUAAAUAUGGAAAAUAAAUUACAUUAUUUGUAAGUGUUGUAAUUUAUAAUGUAAAGAGAAAAUUACAUGUAUACAUGAAAGGAGUGAGAAAGUACAUCAUUUCCAAAUUUAUUUUGAGGUGUGGGAGAAAAAUGUUUCAAGGCCUCAUCCUUAGGGAUCUGUGCUCCCGGGACCCCUCUGACUUCAUCUCCUGCCUGUGUCCUCCUCACUCCCUCUGCUCCAGCCAUACAGGCCUCUUUCCUUUUUCUGGGACUGAGGUUGCUCCUAUCUCAGGGACUUCUCCUGGGCUGUCCCUCUGCCUAGGACUCUCUGGCCCCUCAACUGCAAGUGACAAGCAGCCUUUCUUCCCUAAGUCUUUGUUCUGAUAUUACUUUCUCUAUGGAAACCUUUGUGAUCUCCCACAGCCCCCCACUUGACAUUGCAGCGCCACCUUCACCCCCACCUCUGGUCCAUGUUGCCUGUUCUGUGUGAUUCUUUUAGCUCCUUCACCGUUCACUGGAUCCUGGUGAGAACAAGUCCGUAAGCGGAGAGCAGAAUCAGAAGGUGGGGCUGUGCUGGGCUGGCGCCAUCUGAGUGGAGCUCAACCCUGACUUCACAUUACAGUUUUCAGGCAUUUUGCAAAUAUAUCUUUUGUUCUGUUUUAUCAAAGAUUGCUAUUAUCAUAGGAUGGGACACACCCUCAAUAAUACAAUGGCACUGGUGAUUCUCAUCUGUGUCCAGCAUUGAACAUCAAGGCAGUUUCCUCCAUAUUGAGAACUGAGAUCAGCCUGUGAUCCACAGGGAGGAUUGAUUUCCAAAGACUCAUGCUAUGUAAGGAAGCCACCAAGAAGGGCAAAGAAAAGGAGCCAGGGACGGCUCUUCCUCAGGGACACUAGACUUUCAGGGAUGUGGCUAUAGAUUUCUCUUUGGAGGAGUGGAAAUGCCUGAACCCUGCACAGAGGGCUUUAUACAGGGAAGUGAUGUUGGAGAACUACAGGAACCUGGAGUUUGUGGAUAGCUCUUUAAAAUCCAUGAUGGAGUUCUCAUCAACUGGGCACGGUAAUACAGGAGAAGUGAUUCACACAGGGACGUUGCAAAUACAUGAAAGUCAUCACACUGGAGAUUUUUGCUUCCCAGAAAUCAAGAAAGAUAUUCAUCACUUUGAGUUUCAGUGGCAAGAAAUUUAAAGAAAUGGCCAUGAAGCACCCAUGACAGAAACCAAAGAGUUGACAGGUAGUACAGACUGACGUGAUCAAAGACAUGCUGGAAACAAGCCUAUUAAAGAUCAGCUUGGAUCAAGCUUUCAUUCGCAUCUGCCUGAACUCCACAUGUUUCAGACCCAAGGGAAAAUUGGUAAUCAAGUGGAGAAGUCUAUCAAUGAUGCUUCCUCAGCUUCAACAUCCCAAAUAAUUUGUAGGCUCAAAACCCAUAUUUCUAUUAAGUAUGGGAAGAAUUUCCUCUAUUCUUCAUUAUUCACACAAAUACAAGAAGUACACAUGAGGGAAAAACCUUUCCAAUGUAAUGAGUGUGGCAAAGCCUUUAAUCAUAGCUCAUGUUUAAGGAGACAUCACGUAACCCAUUCAGGAGAGAAACAGUAUAAAUGUGAUGUAUGUGGCAAAGUCUUUCAUCAGAAGCAAUACCUUGCAUGGCACCAUAGUGUUCAUACUGGAGAAAAACCUUACAAGUGUAAUGAGUGUUCCAAGACCUUCAAUCAGAAGUCAUCCCUUCAGUGUCAUCAUAGACUUCAUACUGUACAGAAACAUUACAAAUGUGAAGAAUGCAACAAAGUUUAGAGUUGAGGAUCACAACUUGAAACACACAGGAGAAUUCAUACUGGAGAAAAACCAUACAAACGUAAGGUUUGUGACAAGGCUUUCUGGGAUAAUUCAUGCCUUUCAUGCCGUAAGAGUUCAUACUGGAGAGAAAUGUUACACAUGUAACGAAUGUGGCAAGGCUUUUAGUAGAAAAGCAAACCUUGCACAUCAUGGACUUCAUACUGGAGGGAAAUCUUACAAAUGUAAGGGUUGUGACAAGGUUUUCCACCAUGAUUUAUGCCUUGCACAACAUCAGAGAGUUCAUACUGGAGAGAACCUUACACAUUUCACGAGUAUGGAAAGACCUUUGCUCAAAAUUCAGCCCUUGUAAUGCAUAAGGCAAUUCAUACUGGAAAGAAACCUUACACAUGUAAUGAAUGUGGCAAGGUUUUUAGUAGAAAAGCACACCUUGCAUGUCAUCAUAGACUUCAUACUGUCUAAGGUUUCUAAUCAACAAUCAAACCUUGCACAACAUCAGAGAGUUUAUACUGGAGAGAAACCUUACAAGUGUAAUGAGUGGGGCAAAGCCUUAAGUGGGAAGUCGUCACUUUUUUAUCAUCAAGCAAUCCAUGGUGUAGGGAAACUUUGCAAAUGUAAUGAUUGUCACAAAGUCUUCAGUAAUGCUACAACCAUUGCAAAUCACUGGAGAAUCCAUAAUGAAGACAGAUCUUACAAGUGUAAUAAAUGUGGUAAAAUUUUCAGACAUCGAUCAUAUCUUGCAGUUUAUCAGCGAACUCAUACUGGAGAGAAACCUUACAAAUAUCAUGACUGUGGCAAGGUCUUCAGUCAAGCUUCAUCCUAUGCAAAACAUAGGAGAAUUCAUACAGGAGAGAAACCUCACAAGUGUGAUGAUUGUGGCAAAGUCUUGACUUCACGUUCACACCUCAUUAGACAUCAGAGAAUCCAUACUGGACAGAAAUCUUACAAAUGUCUUAAGUGUGGCAAGGUCUUCAGUCUGUGGGCACUCCAUGCAGAACAUCAGAAAAUUCAUUUUUGAGAUAACUGUUCCAAAUACAGUGACUAUAGAAGAUCAUAAAGCUUUAAUUGACAUUAGAGCCAAAUAGGCAUUGACUUGAGAUUGAGUUGACUUAACCUUGAGUUUAAGAAUUAAUUUACAUUAAAGUGUUUAUGUUAAGAAGAUUGGGCCAGGUGGGGUGGCUCAUGCCUGUAAUCCCAGCACUUUGGGAGCCCAAGGCUGAUAGAUCACAGCCACACCUGGCUAUGAGAGUGUGUAGGUGGCCGUUGGGGUGGGACCUGAUUAGAAGGGGCAGGGCCUUGAACAGAAUCUGGGCGGGGCAAGAAUGAGGAGGCUGCCUGGAGGCCGGGCCAGAGGGUGAUCGUCAUCUUGAGGGCAAGGUCUGGAAGUGGUGUUUUGAAGGGCAGGGUCUCGAGGGGGCGGGUCCUGGCUUUCUCCUCAGCUGGACCCCAGGUGUCGUCUGCUGUCAUCCUCUUGCCCUGCAGGACUAGAUUCUCCGGGUACUAAUUGGUGGAUAGUUUCUGAUGUGCCGUGAUAUUACCCCUAAUAUCACAGGGAUGCCUCCUGUCCAUUUUAGAGACUUGCUCUGUCGCCCAGGCUGGAGGGCAGUGGCGCGAUCUCGGCUCAUUGCAAGCUCCGCCUCCCGGGUUCAUGCCAUUCUCCUGCCUCAGCCUCCCGAGUAGCUGGGACUACAGGCGCCCGCCACCAUGCCUGGCUAAUUUUUUGUAUUUUCAGUAGAGACGGGGUUUCACUGUGUUAGCCAGGAUGGUCUCGAUCUCCUGACCUCGUGAUCCGCCCGCCUCGGCCUCCCAAAGUGCUGGGAUUACAGGCGCGAGCCACCGCGCCCGGCCCCUAAGUUAAUAUUUCAAACAAUCGAAGGUAAAACAACAUAUUGUGUUGGGCCACCUGUACUGAACGCUGAAUCGUUUUUCCUCUUAAGUUGAAAAUGGUUUUAAUGCAAAGCGCCUUUUUUGAGCAGGUAGAGUCACGCAUCCGGCAGGCGGGGCGAGCUCCCCUCUGUCUGGGGCAGGGUGGGGGAGAGGGGCAGGGACCUCGGUAAAGGGGUGGAGUGGCGCGCUGGUUGCCGCGGGCACUGGCAAUUAGAAGGGAUUAUUAAACUAAGCAAGGUCCUGGGUUGUUUGAGUGGAUAAUGGAAACUGAAAGGUGACGUGCAAAACUGCCUAUUACUCCCAGGAGUGGAGGAUAAUUUCAUAUUUCAUGGAAAUAAACUCAGGGCCCGGAGCGGUGGCUCACACCUGUAAUCCCAGCACUUUGAGAGGCCAAGGAGGGAGGAUCGCUUAAGCCCAGGAAUUCGAAAUCAGCCUAGGCAACAUAGUAAGACCUCAUCUCUACUAAAAAUAAAAAAAAACAGCCAGGUGUGUUAGUCCACACCUGUGGUCCCAGCUGCUUGGGGUGCUGAGGUGGGAGGAUCACUUGAGCCAGAAAGUUGGAGGCUGCAGUGAGCUCUGAUCUUGCCACCACACUCCAGCCUGGGUGAAAAAGCUAGACCCUGUCUCAAACAAGCAAAUAAAUGAGAGGUAUAAGUCCUCCUUUAAAAGUAAAGGAAGAGAUUUUUCUUUCCUUUUGUCUCUUAGAACAUUCAAUUAGAAAAUUUGUAAAUUCAUUUUCUCUGUCUUCUGAGGUUUUUUUUUUUAGACAGAGUUUUUCUCUUGUUACCCAGGCUUGAGUGCAAGCCACGAUCUCGCCUCACCACAACCUCCGUCUCCCGAGUUCAAGCGAUUCUCCUGCCUCAGCUUCCCGAGUAGCUGGGAUUACAGGUAUGAACCACUAUGCCCGGCUAACUUUGUUUUUUUUUUUUAGAAAUUAAACCUUUUUUCAGCUUAAUGACCCAGGGGUGUAUUUUUGAAGGACUUGGGAGCUCUCUUUGAAAGGCAAACAACAAGGGAAACAGUACCUUUAUCUCAGUAGGAAAUUAAAUAAUUCAAACAUCAAAUAACUUCAAUUUAAGGCUAUGGACUUUGAGAUAAUUCUGAGCCUUGAGAGGAAUGUGGUCAGGCAACCUGAGUCCAGUGGAAUGCAGGUGCAACUUCUAAGAGUUUUCCUGUAAGUAAUUAAGAAGACUAAGUAGCCCCAGAGAUAAGACCUCCUCGGAUCAUUGUCCCUUCUUAUGUAGUGAUAAAGUAACCUUCCUUGAAGUGUAUCUAUCCGUAAUCAAUCAAGUUGCUGCAGCCUAUGCACUGGCCCAGAAUAAAAAACGUGGUGAUUCUGCUAAAGCUUCUCUGUCUUUCCCUGUGUGUGAAAUCUUAACGUCUCUACUUGGGAACGCUGAUCCCAUUCAUUUAGAGUUGAUGUUUCCACGUGGCUAUUUCCAAGCUUUGCCUUCAAAUAAAUUCUGUACUUAAUCAUAUAUUCUAAAUUUUAUUAUUUACUGCUGACAUCAGUUUCUGUCGGAUUGUAGGAGCCUCACCAGAGAGGGCCCCUGUCGCCAUGUUGUAAAACUCACACUUGCCAAAAGUUGUGGGUUAGGGUUUCUCCCCCUCCCUCAGGAUGACGCUAGUUAGCUGACACAGAUGGUCACCUCCAUUACCAAGUAGAGUCAGGAUGAACUAUGUGUGACUGUUCAACUAUGUGUCCUCUUCCCUGAGGACUGAUUAGUGUUUAUCUUGAAAACAUGUCCUUAAUGGGUUGUAUAGAACACUGAAGCAUCUGAUUUCAAACUCUUAGCUCUUUUCCUCUAUUUCCCAUCACAUUCUGGUCUAAGGCUUAUUUAUUAAUAAAAUGAUUUUUAUUUCUUUA